GCCUUUAAGUUUAACUUAAUACAGUUCAGUGCUGAACUUUAAAAUUCAGAAGGAAAGGGGCACCCGUUUUCCCCAGGAGCUGUAGGUGGACACUGGGCGGCAGCUGCUGCCGUGGGCUGGGCCCAGGACAAGUGGCCUUGGUGUCGGCUGCACACUUGGGCAUUUGGCGAAAAGCAUCAGACUCGAGUCUCAUCUGCUCUCUCACCAGCUUUGCAAAAUCCCGAGGACAAUUUUAUUGGUGUAAUUCUGUCGGAGCUGUGAUGUGUUUCUUGGUCUCUCUACCAUGACCUGGGACCGAUGAUCUAUUACUUUCCUUUGCAAACACUAGAACUCACUGGGCUUGAAGGUUUUAGUAUAGCAUUUCUUUCUCCAAUAUUCCUAACAAUUACUCCUUUCUGGAAAUUGGUUAACAAGAAGUGGAUGCUAACCCUGCUGAGGAUAAUCACUAUUGGCAGCAUAGCCUCCUUCCAGGCUCCAAAUGCCAAACUUCGACUGAUGGUUCUUGCGCUUGGGGUGUCUUCCUCACUGAUAGUGCAAGCUGUGACUUGGUGGUCAGGAAGUCAUUUGCAAAGGUACCUCAGAAUUUGGGGAUUCAUUUUAGGACAGAUUGUUCUUGUUGUUCUACGCAUAUGGUAUACUUCACUAAACCCAAUCUGGAGUUAUCAGAUGUCCAACAAAGUGAUACUGACAUUAAGUGCCAUAGCCACACUUGAUCGUAUUGGCACAGAUGGUGACUGCAGUAAACCUGAAGAAAAGAAGACUGGUGAGGUAGCCACGGGGAUGGCCUCUAGACCCAACUGGCUGCUGGCAGGGGCUGCUUUUGGUAGCCUUGUGUUCCUCACCCACUGGGUUUUUGGAGAAGUCUCUCUUGUUUCCAGAUGGGCAGUGAGUGGGCAUCCACAUCCAGGGCCAGAUCCUAACCCAUUUGGAGGUGCAGUACUGCUGUGCUUGGCAAGUGGAUUGAUGCUUCCAUCUUGUUUGUGGUUUCGUGGUACUGGUUUGAUCUGGUGGGUUACAGGAACAGCUUCAGCUGCGGGGCUCCUUUACCUGCACACAUGGGCAGCUGCUGUGUCUGGCUGUGUCUUCGCCAUCUUUACUGCAUCCAUGUGGCCCCAAACACUUGGACACCUUAUUAACUCAGGGACAAACCCUGGGAAAACCAUGACCAUUGCCAUGAUAUUUUAUCUUCUAGAAAUAUUUUUCUGUGCCUGGUGCACAGCUUUUAAGUUUGUCCCAGGAGGUGUCUACGCUAGAGAAAGAUCAGAUGUGCUUUUGGGGACAAUGAUGUUAAUUAUCGGGCUGAAUAUGCUAUUUGGUCCUAAGAAAAACCUUGACUUGCUUCUUCAAACAAAAAACAGUUCUAAAGUGCUUUUCAGAAAGAGUGAAAAAUACAUGAAACUUUUUCUGUGGCUGCUUGUUGGUGUGGGAUUGUUGGGAUUAGGACUACGGCAUAAAGCCUAUGAGAGAAAACUGGGCAAAGUGGCACCAACCAAAGAGGUCUCUGCUGCCAUCUGGCCUUUCAGGUUUGGAUAUGACAAUGAAGGGUGGUCUAGUCUAGAAAGAUCAGCUCACCUGCUCAAUGAAACAGGUGCAGAUUUCAUAACAAUUUUGGAGAGUGAUGCUUCUAAGCCCUAUAUGGGGAACAAUGACUUAACCAUGUGGCUAGGGGAAAAGUUGGGUUUCUAUACAGACUUUGGUCCAAGCACAAGGUAUCACACUUGGGGGAUUAUGGCUUUGUCAAGAUACCCAAUUGUGAAAUCUGAGCAUCACCUUCUUCCGUCACCAGAGGGCGAGAUCGCACCAGCCAUCACAUUGACCGUUAACAUUUCGGGCAAGCUGGUGGAUUUUGUCGUGACACACUUUGGGAACCACGAGUGGGUUUCUUUGGCCCACCUAAUAUUACACAAAUGCCAAGAAAUGUUAUUAACAAUAGAUGACCUCGACAGGAAACUGCAGGCUAUUGCUGUUUCAAAACUACUGAAAAGUAGCUCUAAUCAAGUGAUAUUUCUGGGAUAUAUCACUUCAGCACCUGGCUCCAGAGAUUAUCUACAGCUCACUGAACAUGGCAAUGUGAAGGAUAUCGACAGCACUGAUCAUGACAGAUGGUGUGAAUACAUUAUGUAUCGAGGGCUGAUCAGGUUGGGUUAUGCAAGAAUCUCCCAUGCUGAACUGAGUGAUUCAGAAAUUCAGAUGGCAAAAUUUAGGAUCCCUGAUGACCCCACUAAUUAUAGAGACAACCAGAAAGUGGUCAUAGACCACAGAGAAGUUUCUGAGAAAAUUCAUUUUAAUCCCAGAUUUGGAUCCUACAAAGAAGGACACAAUUAUGAAAACAACCAUCAUUUUCAUAUGAAUACUCCCAAAUACUUUUUAUGAAACAUUUAAAACAAGAAGUUAUUGGCUGGGAAAAUCUAAGAAAAAAAGUAUGUAAGAUAAAAAGAAGAGAUUAAUGAAAGUGGGAAAAUACACAUGAAGAACCUCAACUUAAAAAACACAUGGUAUCUAUGCAGUGGGAAAUUACCUCCAUUUGUAAACUAUGUUGCUUAAUAAAAACAUUUCUCUAAA